GGAGAACCCGGAUGGAACCCGGGCCUGGCUGAGGCGGAGGUUGUUGCGGAUGCUUCUCUCUCCAGGCGCACCGCAGAUUCCUGCCCGGGGGUUGGACCCGAGGAACCGCCGUCUCUACUGGUUCCGACGGCCAGAGGCUGGGCCCUAGGCUGAGCGGAGAGUGGGACUGGAGCCUGAAACGGGCGCCUAAAAGAAGCCCGUGCAUCCCAUAGGCCUGCGCCUCAGGCUUGGAGACGGGCGGGCGGAGACCGCGCUGAGUCUUUUUUUUUUUUUUCCUAGCAGCUGGCGUUCUUAUCUCACCCGGGAGGCUGUAAAAAUCUCCGUCCUUAACAGUAACACCAUCAGGUCCUAUCAGUUAAGAGCUGCUUGUUAUUUGCAUGCAUUCUUAUAAUUAAAUCUCCUAACAACCCUGUAAGCCACAUUCUCUGGCACAGAACUUUGGAAACUUUGGGGAUCACUUACUUAUCUUGGAGAUAGAAUGUUUUCUAAGCAAAAUUCUGUGGCAUCUCUGGAAUACUACCUGAGAAUUUUUGUGUGCCAUGUCGAAGAAACGCAAAUGGGAUGAUGACUAUGUUCGCUACUGGUUCACCUGUACAACGGAAGUAGAUGGAACUCAGCGUCCACAGUGUGUGUUGUGUAACUCAGUAUUUUCAAAUGCUGACCUCAGACCAUCAAAACUGUCAGACCAUUUUAACAGACAGCAUGGUGGUGUAGCUGGGCAUGAUCUCAAUAGCCUGAAGCAUAUGCCAGCACCAUCUGAUCAGAGUGAAACCUUGAAAGCAUUUGGAGUUGCAUCUCAUGAGGAUACUUUAUUACAAGCAUCGUAUCAAUUUGCGUAUUUAUGUGCCAAGGAGAAGAAUCCUCAUACAGUAGCUGAAAAGUUAGUGAAACCUUGUGCACUGGAAAUAGCACAAAUAGUUUUGGGACCAGAUGCACAAAAAAAGCUUCAGCAGGUACCCUUAUCAGAUGAUGUGAUCCAUUCUAGAAUUGAUGAAAUGAGCCAGGAUAUCUUACAGCAAGUUCUAGAAGAUAUCAAAGCCAGUCCUCUUAAAGUGGGUAUUCAGCUUGCUGAGACAACUGACAUGGAUGACUGCAGUCAGCUAAUGGCAUUUGUGCGCUAUAUAAAAGAAAGAGAGAUCGUAGAAGAAUUUCUCUUCUGUGAACCAUUGCAGCUAUCCAUGAAAGGAAUAGAUGUGUUCAAUCUCUUCAGAGACUUCUUUCUGAAGCAUAAGAUAGCACUUGAUGUAUGUGGCUCUGUUUGUACUGAUGGUGCCUCCUCUAUGCUAGGAGAAAAUUCCGAGUUUGUUGCCUACGUGAAAAAAGAGAUACCUCAUAUCGUAGUUACACAUUGUUUAUUGAAUCCUCAUGCACUUGUCAUAAAGACAUUGCCUACAAAACUGAGGGAUGCUCUGUUUACUGUGGUGAGGGUAAUAAAUUUCAUCAAAGGGAGAGCUCCAAAUCAUCGCCUAUUUCAGGCUUUCUUUGAAGAAAUUGGCAUAGAAUAUAGUGUCCUCCUUUUCCAUACUGAAAUGAGGUGGCUUUCCCGAGGCCAAAUACUUACUCACAUUUUUGAAAUGUAUGAAGAAAUAAAUCAGUUUCUUCACCACAAGAGCAGUAAUUUAGUUGAUGGCUUUGAAAAUAAAGAGUUUAAAAUUCACCUAGCAUACCUUGCAGAUUUAUUCAAACACUUAAAUGAACUCAGUGCAUCUAUGCAGAGGACUGGGAUGAACACAGUAUCAGCUAGAGAGAAGUUAUCUGCUUUUGUUAGGAAGUUUCCAUUUUGGCAAAAACGAAUUGAGAAAAGAAAUUUUACCAAUUUUCCUUUUCUUGAAGAAAUAAUUGUUUCAGAUAAUGAAGGCAUAUUCAUUGCAGCUGAAAUAACACUGCAUCUGCAACAAUUGAGCAACUUCUUCCAUGGAUAUUUUUCCAUUGGAGAUCUUAAUGAGGCAAGUAAAUGGAUAUUGGAUCCAUUUCUUUUUAAUAUCGAUUUUGUUGAUGAUAGUUAUUUAAUGAAAAAUGAUCUUGCUGAAUUACGAGCUAGUGGCCAAAUCCUAAUGGAAUUUGAGACAAUGAAGCUUGAGGAUUUCUGGUGUGCCCAAUUCACAGCAUUUCCAAACCUGGCAAAGACAGCUCUAGAAAUCCUUAUGCCAUUUGCAACUACAUACCUUUGUGAGUUGGGAUUUUCAUCACUUUUACAUUUCAAAACAAAGUCCAGAAGCUGCUUUAAUCUGAGUGAUGAUAUCCGUGUGGCUAUUUCAAAAAAAGUUCCUCGUUUCUCGGACAUCAUUGAACAAAAGCUACAGCUACAGCAGAAGUCACUGUAAGCUGAUAUACUUUUUUAAUGAAUAAUUUCAAUCUUAAUAUCAUUGUAAAAUUAAGCUGUAAUUCUGUCUCUUUCAUAUUUAUGAUAUACUGAAUUCUAUGUCUAAAAAACUUAAGAACUUUAAUUUUGAAUGAGGCAUGUGAAAAUAUGUUUUGAGAAUAAAAACACAGCAGAAAAGAUUAAGUACUACUGCCUAGUUGCUAUCAUGAGAUUUUCCCAAUUCUAAGUAUCUGUUUAACCUGUUCGUGUGGUAUAUGAAAAAGAUACCUAAGCACUAGAAUAUCCAGCUAAAUGGUGCAAUAGGCUAGGAAUUGAGCCAGGAGAAAAGAGAAGAUAUCCCAGAAGUCAAAAAGGCAAAAUGAAAGAUUGAGUUCGCCCGUCUUUGUUAUGGAGAGGUUAAUGAAAUCAGAAGAGGAUUAUGAAAUAUAAUGGGAAAAGGAAUGAUCUGGCUUAUGUAAGACUUACUUUUAAAUAUACUCUUUGGAGUUAGUCUCACAAUGUCCAUUCCCCUAGCUCCUGUGCUAUGAAUAUCAUAUUAAUAAAUAGCCUAAUAUAUUAA